GCUCACGGAGCGGCUGGCUAGGCUGAGGAGAGCUCGCCGGGCUCUGAGGCGCAGGAAUUCAAUAAAGAAAAUGGCAGCUCUUACUCCAAGGAAGAGGAAGCAGGAUUCUUUGAAGUGUGACAGCCUUUUACACUUCACUGAAAAUCUGUUUCCAUCACCUAAUAAAAAGCACUGUUUUUAUCAAAACAGUGAUAAAAAUGAAGAAAACCUGCAUUGCUCUCAACAAGAGCAUUUUGUUUUAAGUGCGCUCAAAACAACUGAAAUAAAUAGACUGCCAUCAGCAAAUCAAGGCUCACCAUUUAAAUCUGCGCUCUCCACUGUAUCUUUUUACAACCAAAAUAAGUGGUACCUCAAUCCACUGGAGAGAAAGCUGAUAAAAGAGAGUAGAUCUACUUGUCUAAAAACUAAUGAUGAAGAUAAAUCUUUUCCCAUUGUGACAGAAAAAAUGCAAGGAAAACCAGUCUGCUCCAAGAAGAACAACAAAAAACCACAGAAGAGUUUAACUGCUAAGUAUCAACCAAAGUAUAGACACAUCAAGCCUGUAUCAAGGAAUUCUAGAAAUUCCAAGCAAAAUCGAGUGAUCUAUAAGCCAAUUGUGGAGAAGGAAAAUAAUUGUCAUUCAGCUGAAAAUAAUUCCAAUGCUCCUCGGGUUCUGAGCCAAAAAAUAAAACCACAAGUUACACUCCAGGGUGGAGCAGCAUUUUUUGUUAGAAAAAAAUCUUCUCUUAGAAAAUCGUCCCUGGAAAAUGAGCCGUCACUGGGACGCACCCAAAAGAGUAAAUCAGAAGUCAUUGAAGAUUCUGAUGUAGAGACUGUCAGUGAAAAAAAAACUUUUGCGACAAGGCAAGUGCCAAAGUGCUUGGUCCUAGAAGAGAAAUUGAAAAUUGGACUACUGAGUGCAAGCAGUAAAAAUAAAGAGAAAUUAAUAAAGGAUUCAUCAGAUGACAGAGUUUCUUCAAAGGAACAUAAAGUUGAUAAAAAUGAGGCUUUUUCUUCAGAGGAUUCUCUUGGUGAGAAUAAGACAAUUUCUCCUAAGUCCACUGUCUAUCCAAUCUUCAGUGCAUCUUCAGUCAAUUCAAAAAGAUCUUUAGGUGAAGAACAGUUUUCUGUGGGAUCUGUCAACUUCAUGAAACAGACCAAUAUCCAGAAAAAUACUAAUACCAGAGAUACAAGUAAAAAAACAAAAGACCAGCUCAUCAUCGACGCUGGUCAGAAACAUUUUGGGGCUACUGUGUGCAAGUCUUGUGGUAUGAUAUAUACUGCUUCCAACCCUGAAGAUGAAAUGCAGCAUGUACAGCAUCACCACAGGUUUCUGGAAGGAAUCAAAUAUGUGGGUUGGAAGAAAGAACGUGUAGUAGCAGAGUUUUGGGAUGGGAAAAUCGUGUUGGUUCUGCCACAUGAUCCAAGCUUUGCUAUCAAAAAGGUAGAAGAUGUCCAAGAACUUGUUGAUAAUGAAUUGGGCUUCCAGCAAGUUGUUCCUAAAUGUCCAAACAAAAUAAAAACUUUUCUUUUUAUAUCUGAUGAAAAGAGAGUAGUUGGGUGUUUAAUUGCAGAACCCAUCAAACAGGCAUUUCGUGUCCUGUCUGAACCAAUUGGUCCAGAAUCCCCAAGCUCUACGGAAUGUCCUAGGGCUUGGCAAUGUUCAGAUGUACCAGAACCUGCAGUCUGUGGGAUAAGUAGAAUCUGGGUUUUCAGACUGAAGAGAAGAAAGCGCAUUGCAAGACGACUGGUUGAUACCCUCAGGAAUUGCUUCAUGUUUGGCUGUUUUCUCAGCACUGAUGAAAUAGCAUUUUCUGACCCAACACCAGAUGAUUGUAGAAGAUUAAAUAGGUACCAGGAGACAUGAAAGAAUCAUCUUCAACAUUUCUCAAGUAGCUGCUGAUUAUCUCCUUUUAUGGAGGCAUAACAAGCUCCUGGAGGCUUCUACAGAUUCUAAAGGGAAAGAUUUCCUGGGAGGUGAGAAAGCCACUUGAGAGAAGGCUAUUUUGAUUUACUAAUUAAUUCAGUGUAAAGGUAGUCCUGGGCACGGUGGCUCACGCCUAUAAUCCCAGCAGUUUGAGAGGCCUAGACAGAGGUUGCUCAGGAGUUCCAGAGCAGCCUGAGCAACUUGGUAAAACCCUGUCUCUACAAAAAAUAAAAAAAAAAAAAUUAGCCAGGUGUGGUGGCACACACCUGUGGUCCCAGCUACUCGGAGUGGGAGGCAGAGGUGCAAGGAUCACUUGUGCCUGGGAGGUUGAGACUGCAGUGAGCCAUGAUUGCCCCACUGUACUCCAGCCUGAGUGACAGAGCAAGACCCUGUCUCAAAAAAAAAAAAAAAAAAAGCCCUCAGCCAAGUCACAUGUUGCUCUUUUGAGAAUGAGGCAAAUGUCCAAAAAGAUAACAUCUGAGACUUAGAGCAAGUUCUAGAACAAGAAUAAAAAAAAUUUUCUUCCAGUUGGUAGCAGAUUGUCUGCAAUCUUGUGUUGAGGAUUUCUAGGACCUCACCAGACUCAAGGGGCAGUGCAUGCUGGGAUUAUUUUGUAAUGUCUACCAUAGACAAGGGCUGUGAAUUUGCUGGUCUUGUCCUUGGUAUUAGUUUAUUCCUAUUAGAUAUCUCAACUGUAGGAAGUGGAAAUAAAUUUCUCAAUGAAAAGCAAUGGCUUAUGUAUUAAAGAGCCAAUUCAAGAAAGAUCCAGUUCCUGCUUUAAGUCUUAAAGCAGGAACUGCUAUUCCUGCUAGGAAAAGAAUGCCCUGGAGAAGCUGCUCUGUUGGCUUGGCAAAGAAGAGUGACACAUGUCAGAGUGAGGAUAAGAGACCCUAUUGAGUAUCAGGAUGCAAAAUUAUACAUACGUUUUUCUACAAAUUAAGACAACUUCCAAUUUACUUGUCACAUUAUUUUGAUGGAAUAUAUGCAAAUUAAUGUUGUGUCCUAUUGCUUGGUACAAUCUUAUACCAAAAGGCCUUCAGUGAUUUCUAGGCAUUUUUAAAGUUCAGAGUGCAGUUGUUCCUAAUGUUUCUGAGAACGCCCUGUGUCGGUAAUUUUUAAAAUUCUGUCUACACCCAAAUGUAGGUAUACCACCUACAUUGGCAAUUCAGUAAUUUGGAAAAUUCCCAGGGGACUGUGGCUUACAGAAACUACUGAUCCAAAACACUUUAUAGAUUAGCAAAAUAAGGCCAAGAGAGGGAAAGAAACCUCACAUUUACUCAAGUUUAAUGACAACACUCAAAUCAAUGAAGUAUAAAAUAAUGCUGAGACACCUUCUGGUACCCAAAGUGUCCUUUAUUCUUUAUCAUCCUAUUUGAGUUUUAUUGUUUUUACACAGCUGGGAAAUGCUUAAGGUACAAAUUAAUAAAUUUUAAACUCAGUAUGGAAAAUACAUUUAAUAAAUUAAAGCAAAAACCAAAGAUCUGAGGAGAUCCAAGAGAUCAAGACAAUCUGUAACCAGAGUCUGAAGUAUCCAAGGAGCUACUCUUUUUGAGGCAUAUUCUCCUCAGCUUCCAGUUAUCAUUUGAUAAACACAUCAGCAAAAGGUUCAGUGUUUUAAACAAAUGUAGACUUUAUUUUGUACUGUACAAAGUGCUAAUGUCAGUAGAUCCAUUAAAAUAUAGAAUAUUUAAGAAAGAUCAUUAAUAAAAGUAAUGGUCAUUCAAUUUAAUGUUACAGUUUACAGCGUUUUACUGCUAGUGUUUUAAGUCAGCAUGAGCAGUAUCAAAGUACUUAUGUAGCUAGUUUCUAAAACUUUACAGAAAACCCAGUACAAUUCCAAGUGCUUAUAGCCAAUAUAAGCAUAUUUCAUAUUAGAAAUAGUUAUCCAUAUGUUAACAAGAAACUAUGGUCCUCAAAUAUGCCAAUUUUAGAGUCUAAUAACUACUGAUAGUAACUAUGUAAAUAUUUUGGAAUAAACAGUUAUUUACGCAAGCCACACUUCAGCUGAGAUGAUCACUAGACAUCUGUUUCCAGAGCUUCAACAAUGUGUGCAGCAGAAGGACGAUCUUUAGGGUCUUCAUUAGUGCAUACAGAGAAGAGUUCAAUUACUUUCUGGUAUGAUUCAUCCAGUUCUUCCAUAUUAAUAGGUGGCCUAGUUCCCAACGCUGCAUAGUAUGCUUCAUCAUCAAAAUCACUUUCAUCAAAAGUUUUAUCUUGAAGGAGUUAGAGAUUGAAACAAUAAACAAAAUCACUUUAUGUCAUGGAAAAGUUUAAUAGCUCACCCUUCUCCUGAAACAAGAAUUUAUGGUCCAGUAUGCUUUCCAUUCUGCCACAGACAGAAUGGAAAUGUCUUCAAUUGUCCUGCCAUCAAGUAGAUUUGCUUUAGUCUUGGAUUUAUAGGUUAUCGACCCCUACUUUUACCCUUCCUGUGAUAGUUUUCCAAUCAAUCAUUUUCUCAGGAAAGGGGAGUUUUUAAGAUAAUGUUUUGCUUCUCUGGAUAGCCUCAAUUUUUCUCCCUAUUCUCAAUCUAUGUCUCAUUUGUGUGAGAUUAAACCUUGGUGGUACCAAAUCAGUCAUCAGUACUAAUACAUAUCUUAGAAAGAUAAAAUUAUAUAAUCUUUAGUGUGAAAUGAAGAGAUUGGGAUUUAUGUUAGAAAUUGUAUUCAUACCUUCAUCAUCAUCAUCAUUUGAAAGAUUAAUGUGUGGAAUCGAUAAAGUCAUCAUUUCCCACAAAGUAAGGCCAAAGGCAAAUAUGUCUGCCUUGUCAGUAAUAACACCAUUCUCCUCCACAGCUUCUUUGGGUUUCCAUGGCUCUGUGCCAAUGUAACAAGCCUCAGGGUCAGUCACUGAAACAAGCAAGAUGGUUAUGAAGGCAGGAGCUACAAAUCACGAAAAGGCAAGCAACCCAAAGGGAAACAGGCGAACGAUUUGAACAAGUAGUUCACAGGUUAAUCAGUGUAGCCAGAAAAUGUAAAAAUACACUCAACCUCAAUAAGGAUUACUUUCUACCUUUCAGGUUGGUAAAUAUUCAAGAAGCUGGUCAGUUGGCAGGUAUGUAGAGAAACAGCAAUUCUCUUACAAAUUAGUAGGAAUAUAGAAUGUGGAUGUUGAGAUUACAGACUCUGGAGCCAGACUGCCUUGCUUGGGUUGGUUCAAAGACAUGUGUGUGCAAGCUGCGUGACCUUGAGCAGAUCACUUCUAGACCUGAAUUUCUUCAUUUUGUGAACAAUAUUAGGCUGAGAGAAGUACCAUUUCUAUGCUUCCAUGAUUGCUAUGUCAAGGAAAAGGGAAAGGGACCAAUCACACAUAGGCUCUUUUUUAAAGCCCAAGAAAGAAAUAGGUCCACUCACAUUUCCAUUUAAACUUGAGUCAACUUGUCAAUUUCAAUGAAAAAGCCAGCUAAAAUUCUCAUUAGGAUUGGACUAAAUCUCUGGAUCAAUUUAGUAAGCAUUAACAUCUUAAUAGUAUUGAGUCUUCCAAACCGCAGUCAUAUAUUUCUCCACUUAGUUAUAUCUUACUGAAUUUUCUCAGUGAUGCUUUAUAGUAUUCAUUACAGAGGUUUUAGACUUUUUUGGUUAUUUAUUCCGAAAUAUUUUGGGUUUUGGUACUUGUAAAUAGAUUUUAAACAAUUCCAUUUUCAAUUAUAUACUGCUAAUACACAGAAAUGUAAUCACUAACUUCACUAUAGCUGUUUUAUAGAUUCCUUGGGAUUUUCUACCUAAACAACAUAUCAACUGCAAACGGGGACAGUUUCGUCUCCUUUCCAAUUUUGCCUUCUCCAUUUUCUUGCCUUAUUUUAGUGGCUAGGGCUAUAGGACUGCUAAAUAAAACUGGCAAGAGCAGGCAUCCUGGUCUUGUUCCCUACUUCAGUAUGAUACCUGCAGGUUUUUCUUGUAGACAGCCUUUUUCAAGCUAAGAUCCCUUCUAUUUCUAGUUAGCUGAGAGGUUAACUAGAUUUUAAACUAACUUUUAAAUCAAGAAUGGAUGUUGGAUUUUGUCAAACACUUUUUCGGUAUCUAUUGAGAUAUGUAGUUUUCAAAUUUGAUUAAAGACUUAAAUGUUGGACCUAAAACCAUAAAAACCCUAGAAGAAAACCUAGGCAAUACCAUUCAGGACAUAGGCAUGGGCAACGACUUCAUGAUUAAAACACCAAAAGCAAUGGCAGCAAAAGCCAAAACAGACAAAUGGGAUCUAAUUAAAGAGCUUCUGCACAGCAAAAGAAAGUACCAUCAAAGUGAACAGGCAACCUACAGAAUGGGAGAACAUUUUUGCAAUCGACCUAUCUGACAAAGGGCUAAUAUCCAGAAUCUACAAAGAACUCAAACAAAUUUACAAGAAAAAAAAAAAAAAAAACAUCAAAAAGUGGGCAAAGGAUAUGAACAGACAACUUCUCAAAAGAAGACAUUUAUGCAGCCAACAGACAUGAAAAAAUGCUCAUCAUCACUGGUCAUCAAAGAAAUGCAAAUCAAAACCACAAUGAGAUACCAUCUCAUGCCAGUUAGAAUGGCAAUCAUUAAAAAGUCAGGAAACAACAGAUGCUGGAGAGGAUGUGGAGAAAUAGGAAUGCUUUUACACUGUUGGUGGGACUGUAAACUAGUUCAACCAUUGUGGAAGACAGUGUGGCAAUCCCUCAAGGAUCUAGAACUAGAAAUACCAUUUGACCCAGCAAUCCCAUUACUGGGUAUACACCCAAAGGAUUAGAAAUCAUGCUACUAUAAAGACACAUGUACACGUUUAUGUUUAUUGUGGCACUAUUCACAAUAGCAAAGACUUGGAACCAACCCAAAUGUCCGUCAAUGACUGGAUUAAGAAAAUGUGGCACAUAUACACCAUGGAAUACUAUGCAGCCAUAAAAAAGGAUGAGUUCAUAUCCUUUGCAGGGACAUGGAUGCAGCUGGAAACCAUCAUUCUCAGCAAACUAUCACAAGGACAGAAAACCAAACACCACAUGUCCUGACUCAUAGGUGGGAACUGAACAAUAAGAACACUUGGACACAGGGUGGGGAACAUCACACCCUGGGGCCUGUCAUGGGGUAGGGGGGAGGGAUAGCAUUAGGAGAAAUACCUAAUGUAAAUGACUAGUUAAUGGGUGCAGCAAACCAACAUGGCACAUGUAUACCUAUGUAACAAACCUGCACAUUGUGCACAUGUACCCUAGAACUUAAACAAUUUUGUUAAUAUGGUGAAUUUUAUUGACUCCUCCCCCAAGCUUUGAGGUAUAAUUAACAAAUUAUAUAUGUUUAAGGUAUACAACUUGAUGUUUGAUAUAUGUAAACACUGACCUCAUAGCCACAGUCAAGCUAAUUAACAUAUCUAUCACCUCAUAUAGUUACCAUUUUUUUGUGUGUGUGAGAAUACUCAAGAUCUACUCUCAGCAAAUCUCAAGUGUACAGUAUUAACAAAGGGCACGAAGCUUCCAUUAUGCAGGAUGAGUAAGUUCUGGUGACCUAACGUACAGCAUAGUGAGGACAUUGAUUCUUGAAUGUUACAACUUUUCCUUCCUGGAAUAAGUCCUAGUUGGUCAAGAUGUAGUGUUCUCAUGUAGUAUUAGACUGAAUUGGCUAAUAUUUUGUUAAGGAUUUUGAUACCUGUGUUUGUGAAGGAUAUUGGACUAUGAUUUUUUUUUCUUAUCAGUUUAUUUUUCUGUGUACAUAGCAGGUGUACAUGUUUAUGUGUUAAUGUGAUAUUUUGAUGCAGGCAUGCAGUGUAUAAUAAUCACAUCAGGACCGAUAGGAUGUCCUACAAUGUGUCAGGUUUUCAUAUUAGAGUUAUGCUGACCACAAAAACAGACUGGGCAGAGGUCCUUAUUCCUCUAUUUUCUGAAAAAGUUUGUGUAAAAUCCAUAUCAUUUCUUCCUUGGAUAUUUGGUAGAAAUCAACAGUAAAACAUCUGGGUCUUGAGUUUUCUUUGUGGGAAUGUUUCUUAGUAGACAUAGGGCUAUGUGGAUUUCCUUUUCUUCCUAUAUUAAUUUUGGUAAAUUGUAUUUUUCAAAGAAAUUGUCCUUUUCAUCUAAGUUGUCAAAUUCAUUGCCAUAAAGCCGUUUAUAAUAGCCUAAUUAUUCUUUAAAUGUGUGUAGAAUUUACAAUAACCCUUUUCUCAUUCCUGUUGUUGGUGACUUGUGUUCUCUUUUUUCUUGAUCAGUCUAGAUAAAGCUUUAUAUAUUUCAUUAUCUUUUCAAAUAACCAGCUUUUGGCUUUGUUAAUAUUUUAUAGUAUUUGUUUUUUAUUUCAUUGAUUUCUGCUCAUAGCUUUAUUCCCUUCCUUUGGAUUUGCUCUGCUUUUCUUUUUCUAGAUUAAAUCAAUGAACAUAGGUCAUUGAUUUAGAACUUUCCUUUUUUCCAAUAUAAUUUACAACUAUAGAUUUCCCUCUGAGCCCUGCUUUAGCUAUUGCUUGCACAUUUUGAUAUGCUGUAUUUUCCUUAAUUAUUCAAAACAUUUUCCAAUUUCCCUUGUCAUUUUAUUUGACCCAUAGGUUAUUUAAAUUUGUGUUACUGAAUUUCCAAAUACUUGGGGUUUCCUUAGAUAUCUUGUUAGUGAUUUCUAACUUAAUUCCAUUGUGGCCAACAAAUAUACUCUAUGAUUCCUCCCAUAGUGUCAUACAAACCUUUACUUCUGCUAUAACUAGGAUAAACUCAAACUCUUACAGACAGAAUAUUCACUAGGCAGUGUUAGAGUGUAUUAUACUAAAAAAUGAAAAUUUUCAGUAUUUGAUUACUAUAAUCUGCAUUUCCUCACAAAUAAGGUUAGAGUGAAAACAAUAUAAUUCAUUUUGAAACAAUAGAAAGAAGACACAGUGGGGCUGUUUACUGAAAGAAAUUUCUCCAGAACUGAAGGAAAGUUCUGCCCUGAGAGUCUCAAGAACUUUACAAGGAAAAGAGGAUGAAACUAACAUUUAAAGAACAAAAGGGAGGGGUAAAAGAAGGAAAAGUGAGAAUCCAUAAGCCAGGAAAUUGAAGAUUCCAGUUAACAAGCACUCAUUUAUUCCGUUAACAUUUUGAGAGGUAUGCCUGAUAAAUGAGCAGGCUCUGUUAAGUGAGAACAAAAAUACCAGACUAGGAGGGUACCCAGUACCAGCAGGCAAGAAGGAAAGAUGAGUGGUGUCUCUAUGGUAGCCUUUGUACUUAGUUCUGCUUUGGGCAUUACAGUUUAGAAGGUAGCCAUGGACAUUAUAAGCUCCUUAAAGGUUUUCCCCUAUACUGUACCUUAUAUAUUAGAGGUACUUCAUGGAAUUCAUGACAAGAGAAAAGCCUAUAGACAUGGCCCACAUGGGCAGUGACUCUGUGGCAAUAAGGAAGGAUACUUACACCGUUCAGUAUAUACACGUAUAUGUGUGUGUACACAUACAUUCUAAGUAGGUCAGAUUCCUACAAGGAUCCAUCAGGCUAAAAAGUAGUUUUCUAGAACUCUGGGUCUAAAAUAACGGCUCCAAUUUGAGACUCGAACCACAAGUGCAUUUCCUGUAUGUAUGUUUACAGUUCUCCAAGUCUGUAAACAUAAUAGCAUGUGACAUAGUGAAUUUAACAUAGUAUUUAAACAUAAUGGAUUGGGCCCCCUGCCACCUAUGUUAGUGAUUGGGUUUGCUCCCUGUGAAGAUGGAUUGUUCUGACAACAAAAGUUUGAUGAGAUCAUAAACUAAUGGUUCAGUCAUUUCUUUUGGUUGAUACAGAAACAGUUUAUACUUUAUUUCCCUUUACUACAUUCAAAGAGUUUAAGCAGACAUGCUUUAGUUACUAUCCCAAACUGAAAAAUGAUGAAACUGGAGCUCCUACUUAUCCUUCAAUUCUCAGCUUAUUAAACAUCAUUUAGCGAGGCCUUCCUCAACAUCUAGACUAGGUUAAGGGCCACUGCUGUGUUUAUAAUUCCUUGUAUCAUAACUGUCAUCUUGUCUCAUUAGUAUUCAAAAGCUGCUUUCCAUCCUAGAUUAGGAGCUGCAACAGGGUAAGACUGUGUCUGUCUCAUGUACUCUAUAUUCAUGGUGCCUGACAUGUAUAUAGUAUUAAUAUUUGCAAAUUUAUCUUGAGAUAAACACUUAAGAUUUUGGCUUUUCAUCGAAUACUAUAUAUAUAUAUAUUUAUUUAUUUAUUUAUUUAUUUUAAUUUAUUUUUUUUUGAGAUGGAAUCUCGCUGUCGCCCAGACUGGAGUACAGUGGCUUGAUCUCAGCUCACUGCAAGCUCUGCCUCCUGGGUUCACGCCAUUCCCCUGCCUCAGCCUCCUGAGUAGCUGGGACUACAGCUGCCCGCCACCACGCCUGGUUAAUUUUUUGUAUUUUUAGUAGAGACGGGGUUUCACUGUGUUAGCCAGGAUGGUCUCAAUCUCCUGACCUCAUGAUUUGCCCGCCUCGGCCUCCCAAAGUGCUGGGAUUACAGGUGUCAGCCACUGCGCCCAGCCAGAAUACUAUAUUUUAGUUGUGAAAUGUUAAUAUAUUACCUGUUUAAAAAAAAUUUUAAGAUUUGGGUAUUUUUUUUCAAACUUUUCUUCAUAUAUGUAAAUACAUAUAAGUGCUAUUUUAUACUCUGUUUAUCUCACUGGAUAUAUUUAUGCCUAUAAAUAUAAACCCGUAUAAUUUAUGGAUAUAUGGUAUUCUAUUGUGUGGUAGUAUAAAUUAAACCACCCCUUAUUGGUGGACAUUCUCACACAUUGUUGCAUAGUCUGUUCUGCUACAAUGUGUAUUUUUGAAACAGUAAAAAGAUUGAUAUUUUUCCCAGUACAUAAAUGUUAUUUUUGAAGUGAUCAGAGGCAAAUCUCACAAAUAGAAAGCCUUUGCCUACAGAAAUGCCUUCCCUGAGCAUAUGCCUGGUGUAGUAGCUUUAAGAAUUGCUAUUGCUAACUACAAAAGCUGUGAGUGAGUCCAGGUAAAGGAGCUGCCAACACAUUUCCCACACGCUUAAAAAUAUAUAUAUAUUUUUAGUGAGAAAGCCAGAUCAAAUUUUUCAUCUUGAUGAAAAGUAUCUAUUGAAAAUACUCUCAUAUGUAACCUUCAGCAUAAACCCAGGGUUUAUGGCUACAAAGGAACAUUUUAUCAUCAUAGAAAGUUUCACUGAACAGCACUGCUCUAGAAAGUCUUGCUCCGGCUCAGAAAUGACACAAGUCAUUUCUUCUGGUAGAACCUUUCAGACGACAGUUUGGAAAUCUGCAUUUAAAAUAAGAAAAAUAUUUUAAAAUGUUUAUGCCCUUGCAGAUUUAAUGUGUUAGUAUCUUUUAUUAGGAUUAUUAACUGUUUUUGUUACUGCUUUAGUUUUCAAAGUUGCAUAGGUUUUAACCCUGUUUUUUUUUUCUAUAAACCUAGUUAUAUCUUGAAACUUUUGCGCAAUGAAGUUUUGCAGGAAAUAAUAUAUCAGGUUAUUAUAAAAAAAAUGCCUGUACUGCCUAAUUACUCAAUUACUUCUUUGGACUGUGUUCUUAAGAAUGAAACUAUAGGGUCAAAGGGCAUAAACAUUUUUAAAGGUUUUUCUUAUUUUAAAUACAGCUUUCCAAACUGUCACCUGAAAGGUUCUACCACAAGAAAUGACUUGUGUCAUUUCUGAGCUUGAGCAUUUAACUAUCACUGCAAGACUUUCUAGAGCAGUAUUGUUCAAUGAAACUUUCUAUGAUGAUUAAAUCUCCUAAAUCUGCAUUGUCCAAUGUGGUAACCAUUAACCACAUGUAGCUUCUGAGCACUUGAAUUGUGGCUAGGGUGGCUGAGAAAAUAAUUUCAAUGUUUUAAUAUUAAUGUAAAUAGCAACAUGCAGCUCAUAACUACUGUAUUGGACAGUACCACUCCAAUGCUUUUUCACCCUCCCCAUAAUGGUGGCCAUGUUCCAUAUAGUGGCUGUUCCAUCAGUAUAAGUCCUAAAGGGAGAAUGACACAGAACAAGGUGCUAAUGGCCAUGCAGCUUGAGUAAUAAGCCUUGGUUGUUGUAAGUCACUGAAGUUUUUGAGGUCUGUGUUACCACAGCAAAACCUAUUCUAACCUCAGUAAAACAGCAGUUACAAGUUCUACUUAGUGUAUGAGAGGACAUGUUAACCUACAUUGUUGCUCAUACUAGCAAUCUUUUUAUUUACUAGCAAUCUUGUUACUCCUUCAAUAAUAUAUUUACAAGUCAGGCACUAUUCUAGAGUUGAGGAUAUUUCAGUGGACAAGAUAUACAAGGUUCCCUUCUUAGAGCUUACAAGCCUAAUGGAGGAAUGGAGAAACGUUUAACAGAUAAUUUACACAGUGUGAUGAGUGUUGAUAGCAGAUUAUCUCAUUGUUAUUUAGCUUUUAAAACAUUAGUAAGAACAUUACAUAUAUAUUUUCCUAAUUGCCAUUUUUUUCAUUUCUCAACAGUCUCUUCAUAAUAGAGCUUUUAUCUGUUUCUCAUUGAUUACUAAUAACUCUUAAUGCAUUAGAAAUAUUAAAUAUCUUAUACAUUUAUCUCAGUUUCUAAUGUCUUAAGCUCCCUGCCCCUCUCCAACCCACUGUGAUAUAGAAUUCUUUUUUUUUAAAUGGAGGUACCCAUGGCUUUUUAAUGAUGGUUUCUAGCUUUGGUGUCUUCUUUAAAGUCCUCUCCACAGCCAACAUUAAAGAACUAUUUAUCUACAAUUUUUUCUACUGUUACUUUUUCCCCCAAUCUUCAAUAUAUGGGGAUUCAAGUGUAAGGAUAGAAAACAGCUGUGUUUUUUUCUAAAAUGUCCAGAUAACAUCAUUUACUGACUAAACUACCUCUUUUCUCACUAAUACAAAAAUGUCACCUUUAUCACACAACAAAUUCCUCUAUUUGGGAACUAUUUCCUGACUCUCAUGUUCUAUUUUUCUGCCUAUUUUGGCAUGAGUAUCAUCGCUUUAAUUACUGUAGCUUUAUAAAACUUUUUAUCUGCUCAGGAAGAUUCCUCCUCCUUUCAUCGAGUUUUCCCAGCCAUGUUUGAUUGAACAUGUAUCCUCAAAGAGGAACUUCAGAUUAAUUCUGACAUGUUCUAGAAUAGAUCACAUUAAGAUUAUGUAGAAUUUAUAGGCUAUCAAAUUCAUUCAUUUCUGCUUUCUGUUCUUAGGGCGUCAUUUUUUUCAAUUUCAGUUGAAUAUUCAACUUAACUUCAUAAAAGUUAAAUAAUGAAAAUGUUUCCUUUGAGUAGUUUUGAACAUAUCAAAUAGGGUUUGACUUGUUAUAUUCUUAUAUUUUCUAAAUAUUUUAUAAAUGGAAUUUGAUUUCUCUUUUUAGCCAAAAAUUAUUCGGAAGUGUUUUAAAUUCCUAAAAAGUUUGGAGUUUUUGUUUCCUAUUUUAUUACAAAUUUCUAGAUUUACAGCAUUGAUGUUAAGGAAUAUCACCUAUUAGACUAUUCAUACUUUUUAUAAUUCGAAGUUUUUUUGUGUGAUCUAAGAAUAUGGUCAAUUUUAAUAAAUAUUAUGGUGCAGAGGUA